CUCUGCGGCGCGGUCCUCGGAGACACGCGGCGGUGUCCUGUGUUGGCCAUGGCCGACUACCUGAUUAGUGGGGGCACGUCCUACGUGCCAGACGACGGACUCACAGCACAGCAGCUCUUCAACUGCGGAGACGGCCUCACCUACAAUGACUUUCUCAUUCUCCCUGGGUACAUCGACUUCACUGCAGACCAGGUGGACCUGACUUCUGCUCUGACCAAGAAAAUCACUCUUAAGACCCCACUGGUUUCCUCUCCCAUGGACACAGUCACAGAGGCUGGGAUGGCCAUAGCAAUGGCGCUUACAGGCGGUAUUGGCUUCAUCCACCACAACUGUACACCUGAAUUCCAGGCCAAUGAAGUUCGGAAAGUGAAGAAAUAUGAACAGGGAUUCAUCACAGACCCUGUGGUCCUCAGCCCCAAGGAUCGCGUGCGGGAUGUUUUUGAGGCCAAGGCCCGGCAUGGUUUCUGCGGUAUCCCAAUCACAGACACAGGCCGGAUGGGGAGCCGCUUGGUGGGCAUCAUCUCCUCCAGGGACAUUGAUUUUCUCAAAGAGGAGGAACAUGACUGUUUCUUGGAAGAGAUAAUGACAAAGAGGGAAGACUUGGUGGUAGCCCCUGCAGGCAUCACACUGAAGGAGGCAAAUGAAAUUCUGCAGCGCAGCAAGAAGGGAAAGUUGCCCAUUGUAAAUGAAGAUGAUGAGCUUGUGGCCAUCAUUGCCCGGACAGACCUGAAGAAGAAUCGGGACUACCCACUAGCCUCCAAAGAUGCCAAGAAACAGCUGCUGUGUGGGGCAGCCAUUGGCACUCAUGAGGAUGACAAGUAUAGGCUGGACUUGCUCGCCCAGGCUGGUGUGGAUGUAGUGGUUUUGGACUCUUCCCAGGGAAAUUCCAUCUUCCAGAUCAAUAUGAUCAAGUACAUCAAAGACAAAUACCCUAAUCUCCAAGUCAUUGGAGGCAAUGUGGUCACUGCUGCCCAGGCCAAGAACCUCAUUGAUGCAGGUGUGGAUGCCCUGCGGGUGGGCAUGGGAAGUGGCUCCAUCUGCAUUACGCAGGAAGUGGCUCCCAAGAUCCCUCCAGACAUAAAGUCCCACAGCCCCAAAUGCCCUUCUACUGUCACGGGUUGCUAUAUGCUGGCCUGUGGGCGGCCCCAAGCAACAGCAGUGUACAAGGUGUCAGAGUAUGCACGGCGCUUUGGUGUUCCGGUCAUUGCUGAUGGAGGAAUCCAAAAUGUGGGUCAUAUUGCGAAAGCCUUGGCCCUUGGGGCCUCCACAGUCAUGAUGGGCUCUCUCCUGGCUGCCACCACUGAGGCCCCUGGUGAAUACUUCUUUUCCGAUGGGAUCCGGCUAAAGAAAUAUCGCGGUAUGGGUUCUCUCGAUGCCAUGGACAAGCACCUCAGCAGCCAGAACAGAUAUUUCAGUGAAGCUGACAAAAUCAAAGUGGCCCAGGGAGUGUCUGGUGCUGUGCAGGACAAAGGGUCAAUCCACAAAUUUGUCCCUUACCUGAUUGCUGGCAUCCAACACUCAUGCCAGGACAUUGGUGCCAAGAGCUUGACCCAAGUCCGAGCCAUGAUGUACUCUGGGGAGCUUAAGUUUGAGAAGAGAACGUCCUCAGCCCAGGUGGAAGGUGGCGUCCAUAGCCUCCAUUCGUAUGAGAAGCGGCUUUUCUGAAAAGGGAUCCAGCACACCUCCUCGGUUUUUUUUUCAAUAAAAGUUUAGAAAGAAAAAA